ACUCAGGGGUCAGGGCAUCACUGGUCUCGCGUGCGCGUGACCAGGCCCGGUUUCCGGUGCCAGGACCUUUCCGAAGCGUCGAGUGGCCUAACGGUCACAGCUGUCGCCCAUCGGAGAGGCAGGACUACUGCGAGCAGUUUUACCGCGACCUCCGGAGGCCGGCGUGACAGGCUCUGUCACUAAAAUAGGUCUGUCCAGUCGUACUUUUUCCUCACCUUGAACUUUCCGUCACGGGAAUACACGAUUUGGCUUAGGGGCCGGGGCUCUCCUGAGGAGAGAGGGUUUGCUUUGCGGGGAAGAGCGAGUCUUGACUUCGCAGCCUCCAAUUUCAGCCGCGGUGUGGAGGGGGGUGCUUUGGGUGGUCCCCACAGCCUUUCCGGAGUGCCCGCGCGUGUAAGCUUUUGAGAUUUGACAAUUUGUGAAGUGCUUGGUGCUGACUUUCGGGGACGACAGGAUCCUUUUACAGUCAUUCUCCUGUCAGGGGAGGCAGGUGGGGAGCGAGGAAGGAUCCAGAUUUCGUUAACAGAGCUUUGAGUUUAAAGAAUUGACAAACUCCCGAGUUGAUUUCCUGUCAGACCUUUUGCGGUUGAGACAUAGAGUCUGAGGCUUUGAUGGUAACCGCGUUUGAUUUAGAGACAGACUGUGCAGCUUCGCUGUUUUAUUGUAAAUACGUAAAUGAGGAGGAAGAGAAAAACGUAGGGUGUUGGGAGCAGAGGCGGGAGGCGGGAGAUCCUGCGAAAUCGGAGUCCCUUUGGAGUGGGGGAGGCCGUCGAGGCGUGCGAGGGCCCGGCCCCCUUGCCGCGUGGUCGUUAACAGGAAAGGCCCUGAUUUGGUUGGUGGCGGAUCGCGUCCCUCCCUCCUCUCCCCGGCUCUCCCCGAGUGCGGCAAACUGGCUUCAGGUUGACUAAAAGAUAGCGAUUUUCCAAGCAGCUUUGCCGCGCGGUGUUUUCUAAAGCGGGGCGUGGGCUGGGUGCCCUUUUGGGCCUCACUUGUCCGGCCUGCGGCAAGUGCUGGGCGAUGGGAUGCGGUUCUGGCGGCAAAGGAAGGGCUGCCUUUGAGAGUCCCGCAGGAAGGUUUAGAAAGUGAUUGUUCUUAAAACAAACAGAGCGUUUUGCUGUGUGUUCCUCAAAGUGGUCCCGGUGGGAGUGGCGCCUCAUUGUGAGCUGUGCCUUAUCUGAUGAAUUAAUGGCAGGUGAAAGCCUUGCGCCUCCGGAGCGAAUAUUUACGACUUUUGAAAAUGUCUUUAAUGUCUAAAAAAAGUCUUUUAGAAAAUCAGACGGCCUCUUGUUCUUAUGUUAUCAAGAGUUUAGAUUUCUGUGGUAAAUAUAAGUGAGUUUCAUUUUAAGUAAACUCAUUUUACGAGAUUUGAGAUUUGAAAGUGAAAUUAAUUAAUUUUGCACAAUCUAGCCUUGGGCUCUGAGAAAAUGUUGUAAAGCUGUAAUUAAUCUUGUGGGACGAAGUGAAAAGGAACUAAAGUGUAUGGUGUAAUGAAUAGUUUAAAUUUCUGUGGUAAAUACAAGUGAGUUUCAUUUUAAGUAAACUCAUUUUUAUGGGAUUUGAGAUUUAAAAGUGAAAUUAAUUAAUUUCGCACAAUCUAGUCAUGGUUGGGCUCAGAAAAUGUUGUAAAGUUGUGAUUUAUCUUAUGGAAAGAAGUGAAAAGGAAUUAAGGUAUAUGGUGUAAUUAAGAGUUUAAAUUUCUGUGGUAAAUGCAAGUGAGUUUCAUUUUAAGUAAACUCAUUUUUACGGGAUUUGAGAUUUAAAAGUGAAAUUAAUUCAUUUUGCACAGUGUAGUCAUGGUUGGGCUCUGAGAAAAUGUUGUAAAGCUGAAAUUAUUUAUCUUGUGGGAAGAAGUGAGAAGAAACUAAAAUGUGUGGUAUUAUCAAGAGUUUAGAUUUCCGGGGUAAAUAUAAAUGAGUUUCCUUUAAACUCAUUUUUGUGGAAUUUGAGGUUUAAAAGUGAAAUUAAUUUUGUAGAAUCUAGUCAUGGUUGGGCUCUGAGAAAAUGUUGUAAAGCUGUAAUUUAUCUUGUGGGAAAAAGUGAAAAGGAACUUAAAUUUAUGGUGUUAUCAAGAAUUGGCCAGGCGCGGUGGCUCACACCUGUAAUCCCAGCACUUUGGGAGGCCGAGGUGGGCAGAUCACUUGAGGUCAGAAGUUCGGGACCAGCCUGGCCAACAUGGUGAAACCCAGUCUUUACUAAAAGUACAAAAAUUAACUGGGCAUGGUGGUGCAAGCCUGUUACGCUAACUACUCGGGAGGCUGAGGGAGGAGAAUUGCUUUAACCCGGGAGGCAGAGGUUGCAGUAAGCCGAGAUCAUGCCACUGCACUCCAGCCUGGGUGACAGAGUAAGACUCUGUCUCAAAAAAAAAAAAAAAAAAAAAAGAAAUUUAGAUUUCUGUGGUAAAUAUAAAUGAGUUUCAUUUUAAGUAAACUCAUUUUGUGGGAUUUGAGAUUUAAAAAUGAAAUUAAUUUUGCACAUUCUAGUCAUGGUUGGGCUCUAAGGCAAUGUUGUAAAGCUGUAAUUGUUUGCCUUAUGGGAAGAAGUGAAAAGGAAUUAAAAUUUAUGGUGUGUCUACUAUGAACCAGGCAUGAUGCUGAGAGUUUAACUGUGUAAUUUUUGGCCUAAAUAGCCCUGUGAAGUAGAUAUUAUUCCAACUUUACAGGUUAGAAAAUUUGAGGCACAGAGAGGUGAAAUAUUUGCCUAAAGUGAAACGGCAAAUUUGGCAAUUUGGACUUGGAUUCAAGUGUUUAUAACUAAAGCCCAGCUCCUUGCAUCAUACCCUGGUACCUAAAAGACAUAAAAACUCACUUCAGGUGCAAUGUGAAUGAAAAUGACGUUAUGACCCAGGCUUGUUGUCUAUGUGCUCCUUGAGAAAUAGUUCUGUUGGAUAGAUGCGGUCAAUACUCAAAAGCCCUUGCUAUCUUUGCCAUGCAUUACUCUAAGCACUUGACAUGUAUUAAUUUAAUCCUCACGAUUCCGUGAGGUAUGUGCUAUUAUCAUUCCCAUUUUACAGACAAAAAAAAAAAAGGAUUUAAGUAAGUUGUUCAACUUACUUACACAGCUAGUAUGUGGGGGAGGUGGGACCCAAACCCAGGUAUUCUGACCACAAGCCUAAGGUCUUAAUGCUGUUUGAUGCUGCCUCUCAUGUAACCAGAUAUGUGUGACAGUUGCCGUAGAAGUAUUAAAGUGUGAGUGUUAUUGUAGUUCAGGGAAAGCCGUGUCACAUCCACAUGGGAUGAUCAUUGGCAUGGUGCCCUUGCUUUUUGGAGGUGAAACUUGAAGUAAGCCUUGAAGUUGAAUAGAUUCUCCUAGGCGGAGACACAACAGGGUAUUAUGGACGGAGGGCAUAACAGGAGCGAGAAGCUCAAAGAGUGAAAGAUUGGUGUUGAUUUGUAUAUGUACCAGAGAUGUAAACAUGUUGGGAGUCCAGUGGUGGACUCACUGCACAGUGCUCCUGUGUCUAACUACAGCCAAAUUUUGACAACAUUGUUAUUAAUCCAAAUAGGGAGUUCUCUGUUCUCUGGAUGUAAGAGCUUGUAACCAUUGUCUGCAAACUUGCCUGAAACAGGCUACACAGUAAAUAUUUUAGGCUUAGAACUGCUGUCCCCAGUCUUUUUGGCACCAGGAACCGGUUUUGGUUUUGUGGAAGACAAUUUUUCCACAGAUGCAGGGACGGGGGAGUGCUAGCGGGGUAUAGUUUCCUAAUGAAACUGUUUCAUAAGGAGAGUGCAACCUAGAUCCCUCGCAUGUGCAGUUCACAAUAGGGUUUGUGCUCCUGUGCGAAUCUAAUACUGCAGCUCAUCUGACAGGAGGCGGAGCUCAGGCGAUAAUCCUUGCUAGCUCCUGCUGUGCUCCUAACAGGCCAAGGACCAGUACCAGGCGGUUGCCCAGGGGUUGGGGACCCCUGGCUUAGAGUAAAGGGGCAAGUGGUAAGAAGUGACCUCUGCGCAGUGGGCGGGGUCCUGAUUAUGGAAGGACCUUGCAGGCCAUGGUAGGAGUUUGGAUUUUACUGUGUUAUUGGUAGCAAAGGUAUACCAGGUGAUUUUAAUAAUGAAGUAAAGUGCAUAGAGUGUGGUGGUAGACUGCACCAUUUACUAGCAAUGGGACCUGGGCAAAUUACUUAAAUCAAGCUUGUCCAACCCGCCUUAUUUUGUUGUUGUCGUCAUUGUUGUUGUUCUGUUUUGUUUUGUUUUAGGCUUUCGGCAGCCUGAAGCUAUGCUUUUUAGUUUCUGUCUCUAGGGAUAAGUGGAAAAGAGGGAUGAGGAAGGGGCUUUCCUGGCCCAACCAGAAACAAACUAAGAACCCAUGACUAUAUUCCCUCCCUUGGACACCCCUAGUAAACGUUCUUUGCUUCAGUUUCCUCAUAAGGAAAAUGAGGACAGUAAUAGAACCUAUCCCACAGGGUUGUCAGUAAUUUAGCAAGAUAGAAUACCUAAUCAAAGAAUCAAAAGAAAGUACAAAUUAAAUUAGAAAUAAUAAUUUUAAACUGUGGUUUUGCUAAAAAUUCUGUAAUUAUGAUGAAAUGAUUAUCCUUCUGGAUAAAAAUAAUUUGUCAAAACAACUCAAGAAAAAGUAGGAUAAUUUGACUAGAUCAUCAACCAUGGAGGAACUUAGAAAAUGUUAUAAAAACUGGACCCAGAGAGUUUUUUUUAUAAAUUCAACCCUUUGAGCACAAAAAUUGUCGUGCGAUGUAAACUUUUUAGAGUAUAGAAAGAGAUGAAAGGCUUCCCAGCUAAUUUUGCAGAGCAAUUUUGAUACCAAGUGUUAAUAAUGUAGCAAUACAACACUGAUUCAUUAAUUGUGAGAAAUAUACCAUCUCACCAAUGUAAGAUCUUAGAAAUAGAGAUGCAAACAAUUUCUAAAUAAAACACCAACAAAUUGAAUGUUGUUGUUUAUAAUCAGCUGGACCCCUCACCCCAAGAACAUUAAGAAAUGUAUUAAUAUGUUGCAUCAGUAGAUCAAAAGAGAAAAGUCACUUAGUCAUCUGAUGCCAAGAAGCUAUUUGGUACUAUGUAUUAUCUGUCCUGGUUUUAAAACUACAUGCAGGACCAGCAGGAUACUACCUUAGUUUAUUUUGGAACAUCUGGCUGACCCCAACAGCCCUCCUUAGUGGGAAGAAGUAGAGGAGAAUUUUCAAACGUGGAGACCUAUCCAUUGUUUCUACCUCUAGGAAUUUAUCCCAUAGAACUACUUGCACAGGUGCAAGACUGUUCUGCAGUGUUCUUUAUAAGAGCAAAACUUUAGAAGUAACUUGAAUAUCUAUGAAUUGGGGGCUGUGUUUAAUAAAUCAUGGCAUAUUUACAAGAUAGAACACUAAGAAGUCGUUACAGUAACUACAGUAGACCUAAAAGUACUGGUUUGGAAAGACUCUUUCCACCACAGGUUAGUUUUGCCUGUUUUUGAGUUUAAUAUCAAUUGAGUCAUAUACUGUACUCUUUUGUUUCUGGCUGUUUUUAAACCCAAGGUUAUGGUUGUGAGAUUCGGCCUUGCUGUAUACAGCAGUAGUUGGUUUAUUCUUAUUGCUGCGAAGUUCCUUUAUAUAAAUAUACCACAAUUUAAUUACUGAUAGCCUGUAUAAGUUUUAUGGUCAGAAAACUCAAAUAGUUUAAAAAGUGAAAUUUGAUUGAAGUUACAGCCCCAAUUAGAGAGGUAUUUUAUAACUUGAUACUUCUAUGCAACAUUAGUCUGCGUUUAUCUAACUCGAGUUAGUUCUCCCAUCUUCUUUAUCCCUUUUGAUUUCUGUCUUUUGGGUUCAUGGUCAUUAGUAUCUCCACUAUAGAAUGAAAGGGAAACAGGAAAGAGAUGAAACCUGAAUCUCUUAAUUGUGCCUCUCAUUACUGCUCUGGUUCAGAAAGGAUAGGGUAGCUCUUUCAUUAACGUACCCUUCCCAGUAACUGUGAUGCAGACAUUCAAAGCAAAUUUCUAGUACAAGAUAUAAUCCGAUACUCUUGCAGCCAGUUUUCUAGUUCCAUAGUAAAGUGACUCAGAGCCAUAACCAAACCUUCCUAAUUUUAGAUUGUUUGGCUUACCUUUCACAUCCACUUAUUUAGGUUUAAUAUAAAAUUUAAUAAGGCAAUCCUAACUUGAAAGUUGAAAUGGACCUUAGAGAUCAUCUCAACUGGUGUUCGAAACCUGGUGGAUGAGGAGGUGGUGUCUCUUGUGGUCCGCCCAGCCCACAUAGUCGGGGGGGACCCAAUCCAGAAUAGACUCCUGGCUUACAUUUUGGAGGCAAUGCUUUCUCCUUAGUCAAGAGCCUUUUGGAGCUCCUUUACAAAAGCAGUUAGCCCUUGCGUUCUCUUGUUCAUUUGUUUCCAGCAUUUACUCUGUAGGCUUUAAGUUACUAAGCAGUCACUUCACAGUUUGUAAUUGUGUUUGAUUUGAUUCUUAUUUCUAGUCAUGAGCAAUAUGGCCCUUCAGUUUUGAAAGAUUUAUUCUAAAUUGGCCAUGGAAGAAUUCUGGUUUUGUCACUCUCUAAAAUUCAACCCAAAGUCCAAUUCUAUUUGAGUUAGCAUUCUGAGAGUAUAUCCAUAUUAUUAAGGUAGUAAGUGUAUGAAGUAACUUUUUUAUGCGUUGCUUUUCAGGAGUAGAGGUUUACCACUCUUAGGUGACUAAGCAGUAUCACAAAUAAACCCUCCAGCAAGUUUAAAAAUAAUUAGGUCCAACUCAGAGGAAGUGGAGUUUCUCCUGUUGCACAAAAAUGAUGUCUAACAGCUCCAGUGAAAUCGAUGUGAUAAAAACAAGAAUACCUACUUACGAUGAAGAUGACAACACUAUUCUUUAUGCGUAUGAAACAAAACCUGAAUUUGUCAAUAAACAGGAACCGAAUAUUGUAUCUGACGCAUCCUGUAAUACUGAAGAGCAACUGAAGACAGUUGAUGAUGUCCUUAUUCAUUGCCAGGUUAUAUAUGAUGCUCUGCAAAACCUGGAUAAGAAGAUUGAUGUGAUUCGUAGAAAGGUUUCAAAAAUCCAACGUUUCCAUGCGAGAUCCCUGUGGACAAAUCAUAAGCGAUAUGGAUAUAAAAAGCAUUCUUACCGGCUUGUUAAAAAGCUUAAACUCCAGAAAAUGAAGAAAAAUGAGGUUUACGAGACAUUCUCCUACCCUGAAAGUUACAGCCCCACUUUACCAGUGUCAAGGCGUGAGAAUAAUUCCCCGAGCAACCUUCCAAGGCCAUCCUUUUGCAUGGAAGAAUACCAGCGAGCUGAGCUGGAGGAGGACCCGAUCCUCAGCCGCACUCCGAGUCCAGUGCAUCCCUCAGAUUUCUCUGAGCAUAAUUGUCAGCCGUAUUAUGCAUCUGAUGGUGCAACGUAUGGUUCUUCUUCAGGGCUCUGCCUUGGCAACCCUCGGGCUGACAGCAUCCACAACACUUACUCAACUGACCAUGCUUCUGCAGCACCACCUUCAGUUACAAGGUCACCAGUUGAAAAUGACGGUUACAUAGAGGAAGGAAGCAUCACUAAGCACCCUUCAACCUGGUCGGUGGAAGCAGUGGUCCUAUUUCUAAAACAAACAGAUCCUCUUGCAUUAUGCCCUCUUGUCGACCUCUUCAGAAGCCAUGAAAUUGACGGGAAGGCUCUGCUCCUACUCACGAGUGACGUGUUGCUGAAGCACUUGGGGGUGAAGCUGGGAACGGCUGUGAAGCUAUGCUACUACAUUGACCGACUUAAACAAGGAAAAUGCUUUGAAAAUUGAAAAAAUCCUUGUGCAAAUUUAGAUUGGGCCAACUUCUAGAGGCACCAAUGCCUUCUUAGUGUGGAAUCAUUUUUCUGCCCUUUAGUCGUUUUUGUUUUGUAGAAAGUAUCUCUCAAAAUAUAUUAUAGCUAGAAUUGUAGAACUAUGUUAUAGUCCAGUCUACUUCUUUAAAAACCAUUUAAACUGCUAGAUAGUAUUAGAAUAGUCCAAUAGAAAAUUCAUUCUUUAUAGGUCUUUAAAAAUUACUUUUAUUAUAUUGUUUACAAAUAUAUUUCAUGCAAGAAACAGAAAAAAAAAAAAACCCUUUGAUUCUGGUUCAUCUCGAUACAGAGAACCAAAACAGCUAAGAGAGGUAUUAUCAGGGUUGACAACUCCUAUGAUUGAAUCUAUGGGAAUUAUUCCUCAGAAGAGAAUUUAAAGGUGUACCCAUAUAUAUCUCUUUCUGGAGUAUUUUAUCUGUCUGAUGUUGCAGUAUUCUACAAGUUUCCAGAAAGAGAAUAGCCAUAUAAAUUAUUUUCCUUUCUGCUAUUAUUUCUCUAUAUGUUUUAUUUAUUCAGAUUUAGAGUAAAAAAUAAGCAUAUAAACUUUUAUUAUGUGCUCUUAACAGUUUUAAGAUAAACUAUAGGAUAGAUAGAAUGGUUAUUUUAUGCAAGAAAUAUUGUACCGCAAGGGUGGUUUGGAUGAAGUCUGACUACUUUUUUUCAAACAAACUAUUAUAUUAAAACUGUCAUAUUUUGGCUAAGUUUGGACCUAUAACUACACUUUCAUUGUUUGCAUCUCUCUAUGAAGAUACGUCUGUCCAAACUUUUAAAAGGCAUAACUGUAUUUUAUGUGUUUAUUCUUUAUAUAGAUAGUAUUUUAUAUUUUAUUCUCACCCGAAGUAUUCACACAAUCUUUUUAAAAAAAAUUUGAAAUGGCAUUUUGUAUUGCCACAGAGGUAGGAUGAGCCAUAUAUUAGUGAAAUGUUUUAUUUUGUAAAAUAUAAAUGGAUUAUUUGCCAUCAUUAGUACCUCUCAACUUACUUUUUAGAGGACAAGAAACAAUCUGUAGAUUGGUUUCCAUACAGGGAAGUUCUCCGUCCUAUGCAAUGUUUCUAAUUAAUUUGCUUAAUUCUGAGCCAUUAAUCCUGCUACACUUUGAAUGAUACAUUAAUUCAGACUAAUCUUUGGGGGCUUUAUUUUGUAAGUUAGAACUUUCAAGGGAAACAUGUUCAACACUAUUAUUUUGUUAUAAAUUUAUAACUUUGUUAUUACAUUGUGUAACAAAUAUAAGGUUUACGAGCUAUGAGAAUUGGUGCUAUCACCAUUAGCUAUUUGCUGUAAUGUCAAGAAAAUGUUCACCAGAUGCAAGAAUGUACCUUUUCUUUUUAGAAAGCCAAAUGUACUUUAGACAUGAAUGCAACUAUUUAAAGAAUAGCUUCAUCAAUGUUAUUCCUUACAUGUCAUAAGAUUCUUACUUAAACUUGGUCUUCUUUCAAAUUGUUUGUAUGAAGAUGCUGUACCCACUUGAACAGUCCUCAGGUGUUUACAUAAAUACUAUGUUUUACAGUUUUCAUAUUUUAAAAUAUUAAUAAAGUUAAAUCACAAUAGUUCA